GACAGCUGCCCUGGCUCCCUCCCAGCAAGAACCCCCAGACCCUCAUCUCUCAUAAGGAAAGGGACUUCUGGGUCCUUUAAAAAAAAAAAAAAAUCCCACCUCAAUCCCCCAGGGCUCUCCUGCAGCUGCUGGAGAGAGAGAUGCAGAAUGAAUGAACUUCUGGUUUCUGGAGGAGGCACGGGAAGAAAGAUUGGAAACUGACUCUGCUAGAAACUGCUGUUUUGGGGAUUUUUUUCUUCCCCUUCAUCUCCACCAGAAACCUGUCCCUUCCCUGGGCACCAAGAGAUGGGCUCCCCUUGCCUGGCAGAGAAACAGCUGGAAACUGGCUCCCUGAGACAAGAAGACUGGUAAACCCAGCGCUUCCUACCUGGUGGUCUUCAGCAAUGCCCAUGCCUUCCAGAGACGGGGGCCUGCAUCCCAGACACCACCACUAUGGUUCCCACAGCCCUUGGAGUCAGCUCCUGUCCAGCCCCAUGGAGACGCCGUCCAUCAAGGGCCUUUACUACCGGAGGGUGCGGAAGGUGGGUGCCCUGGACGCCUCCCCAGUGGACCUGAAGAAGGAGAUCCUGAUCAACGUGGGGGGCAGGAGGUAUCUCCUCCCCUGGAGCACACUGGACCGGUUCCCGCUGAGCCGCCUGAGCAAACUCAGGCUCUGUCGGAGCUACGAGGAGAUCGUGCAGCUCUGCGAUGAUUACGACGAGGACAGCCAGGAGUUCUUCUUCGACAGGAGCCCCAGCGCCUUCGGGGUGAUCGUGAGCUUCCUGGCGGCCGGGAAGCUGGUGCUUCUGCAGGAGAUGUGCGCGCUGUCCUUCCAGGAGGAGCUGGCCUACUGGGGCAUCGAGGAGGCCCACCUGGAGAGGUGCUGCCUGCGGAAGCUGCUGAGGAAGCUGGAGGAGCUGGAGGAGCUGGCCAAGCUGCACAGGGAGGACGUACUGAGGCAGCAGAGGGAGACCCGCCGCCCCGCCUCGCACUCCUCGCGCUGGGGCCUGUGCAUGAACCGGCUGCGCGAGAUGGUGGAAAACCCGCAGUCCGGGCUGCCCGGGAAGGUCUUCGCUUGCCUCUCCAUCCUCUUCGUGGCCACCACAGCCGUCAGCCUGUGUGUCAGCACCAUGCCCGACCUCAGGGCAGAGGAGGACCAGGGCGAAUGCUCUCGGAAGUGCUACUAUAUUUUCAUCGUGGAGACCAUCUGCGUGGCCUGGUUCUCCCUGGAGUUCUGCCUGCGGUUUGUCCAGGCCCAAGACAAGUGUCAGUUCUUCCAGGGGCCCCUGAACAUCAUCGACAUCCUGGCCAUCUCCCCAUACUACGUGUCGCUGGCGGUGUCUGAGGAGCCCCCGGAGGACGGCGAGAGGCCGAGCGGGAGCUCCUACCUGGAGAAGGUGGGGCUGGUCCUGCGUGUGCUGCGAGCGCUGCGCAUCCUCUACGUGAUGCGCCUGGCUCGCCACUCGCUGGGGCUGCAGACGCUGGGGCUCACCGUGCGCCGUUGCACACGUGAGUUCGGCCUGCUCCUUCUCUUCCUGGCCGUGGCCAUCACCCUCUUCUCCCCUUUGGUCUACGUGGCCGAGAAGGAGUCCGGGCGGGUGCUGGAGUUCACCAGCAUCCCCGCCUCCUAUUGGUGGGCCAUCAUCUCCAUGACAACGGUGGGCUACGGGGACAUGGUGCCCCGCAGUGUGCCAGGCCAGAUGGUGGCCCUCAGCAGCAUCCUGAGCGGGAUCCUCAUCAUGGCCUUCCCGGCCACGUCUAUCUUCCACACCUUCUCCCACUCCUACCUGGAGCUCAAGAAGGAGCAGGAGCAGCUUCAGGCCCGCCUCCGCCACCUCCAAAACACCGGUCCAGCCAGUGAAUGUGAACUCCUGGACCCCCAUGUGGCCAGUGAACAUGAGCUCAUGAACGAUGUCAAUGACCUAAUCCUGGAGGGCCCAGCCUUGCCUAUCAUGCACAUGUAACUCAGCACCCCCCAUGACUACAUGGUAACCUCAACCCAUCACCCUGCCUGAAACACACUCAAGGGUACCCCGCAUAGACCACCUGGUGGUGUUUCUAGAGCCCAGGGAAGACUUUCAAAGCUGGAGGGGCAUAAGGCCACAGAGGCUGUGUGUCUGUGAUCCUUGUCCCUCGGGGCCCCGAUGUCCCAGGCUGACUGUGUCCAGCCUGCUUGCCUUUUCCUCUCUCUGCCCAUCUACUGAGCAUGUCCAAUCUUGCUGGAGUAGCUCAGUCUCCUUUCAUUCUCUUUUCCUUCCCAGCAGAGGCUUUAACAUCCCAGGCUGGGUUCUGGAUGCCCAUAGAACUGGUAACCAUUGGUAUUUGCAUACUGAGCCUAUGUAAUUUCAUGAUUUCCCUAAGACCCUCCUUCCUGGGCCAUGCCACCACUGGAAAUCAAAGGUCCAGUCACUGCAAACCCCUCUAAUCAGAUCUCCCCACCCAACCUUUCCACGGGUUCCAGAGGGAUCAAUAUGUUCUCCUUCUGCUCACCACCACCAGUGAUAUUUCCCUAAUGCUGCUACCUCCCGCCAGCUCUGAACACUUGUAGCUAAGAAGGCAGAAUCAGCCUUUUUGCAGUAAAUCUCAUGUUGAGGCUGAUGCCCCCAAGCCUGCCAUCCUUUACCUGGAGCUCAAGAAGGAGCAGGCAUCCCCAGGCAUGCCUGGGAUCUGUGACCUGGGACCUGGGACCUGGGACCUGGGCAGAAACUCCACUUUCCAGCACAGCCAGGCCCUCCCUGGCCGCCUGGACUCUUGGUGUGGUGUUCUCCAGUUAUCCAGUCCUUAGCCUUGACAGAGACAAACUCUUUCAGGGUCCAUGUUGUCCCUUGAGAGGAUCGUUCCUGCUGCUGGUUGCUCCCACACUGCAGGGGCCUUAGCUUUUCAUCCACAGCUGAGCCCCCAUGGACUCAAUGUAGCUUUGGCACAGAAACAAGGGGAAUUGUAGGUGCUGUCCCUUGCUGGCUUCCCAGACUAGUCAUCUCCAUGCUGGAGGAUAGACAUUCUUAGCUCACAUUUCAAUGUAUUCAUUUCUGCAUUCAUCUGUGAACAGAGUCUGUCCUUUGCAUCCAGGGGAGGAGGCAGAUGGAGGUCUGAGUCACUGGAGAUAAACCAGCAUAUUCUGAGAGCAGGCAGGAAGGAGCAAUGACUUCCAAGCAGUGGGCUCCCAAAGGCCUCACAGAGACAUGGGCAGGGCUGGAGAGUAGAGGUGUAUUUUAGGAGAUGAAGCUGAACAGCUGGGUUGGGUUGAGAAGGCGUGGGCCUUGAAUGCUUUAUGGAGGGCAGAGUGAUGUGCACAGGCUGUGGGUUAGGGAGAUGAUGAGGCUGGAUUGGGCAUGAGAAGCCCAGUUUGGGAUGAGGAGCCAUUGAGCCAUUCAGGCAAGACAGCCCUCCCUCCUUCACGGGCUUAAUCCUGCAAGAUUCUGUCAAAUCCUGGCUUCUCCCAGCAGGACACACCUUGGAGACAUCCUGAUGGCACUUCCCCAGAGUGGCAUGGCCCACAUAGGAGUUUGCUGUUGGCUCUAGGACUCUUGAAGAAAGUGCACAAGAUCAAAACAGGUGACAGUGAAGUGGUUUCGGCCCUGCCAAUCUGAUAUCGUGUACGUAUGAGAGUGGUCAGCAUUUUACCACUGGUAACAAGUUCCUUGCUGUUCAUUCAUUCUGCUAGUUUUUUGCGAUUUCCCGCUGUGUGCCAGGCAUAGUCCUCCACUGAUGGCAAUGCCAGACAGCAGCGUGGCAGAGGGCUCUGGCCCAGGAAGCACCCUGCACCAGCACCUAGCGUCCAGGGAGCCUUGGCCUCCUGGCGAGCCUGCCUUUCCUUGGAGUCCUCCAGGUGUCCCCCCAACUAUACAGGCACAUGUCCCCAUUCUUUUAGACCCCAAUCUUUCCCAAGCUGACAUGUCACCAGGUGACAUAGUGGUUCAGUGGCCAUGACACAAGGAAAGCCCCUUCACCCUAUAAAAUCCCCAGCCUGGAUGGCCACUCCACUCCACAAAGUGACAGGCAGAUUCCCAUAAGCGUUGCGUAGAAAUUCCAUGUCACAGGCACCUUGGACAGUAGCCAUAGAAGUGUUUCUGUUCCAGAGUAACAUUUUAUUUAUUACUUAUUUAUUUAUUUAUUUAUUGACAGAGUCUCUCUCUGUCCGCCAGGCUGGAGUGCAGUGGCUUGAUCCCAGCUCACUGCAACCUCCGCCUCCUGGGUUCAAGCAAUUCUCCUGCCUCAGCCUCCCAAAUAGCGGGGAUUACAGGCACCCACCACCUGUAAUCCCAGCUAUUUGGAGAUCAAAUGCUCAGCUAAUUUGAUAUUUUUAGUAGAGACAAGGUUUCACCAUGUGGACAGGCUGGUCUUGAACUCCUGAUGUCAGGUGAUCCGCCUGCCUCGGCCUCCCAAAGUGCUGGAAUUACAGGCACGAGCCACCGCACCCGGCCCAGACUAACAUUUUUUUUUUUUUUUUUUUUGAGACAGAGUCUCCCUCUGUCACCCAGGCUGGAGUGCAGUGGCUCAAUCUCGGCUCACUGCAAGCUCCGCCUCCCAGGUUCACGCCAUUCUCCUGCCUCAGCCUCCUGAGUAGCUGUGACUACAGGUGCCACCACCACGCCUGGAUAAUUUUUUGUAUUUUUAGGAGAGACGGGGUUUCACCAUGUUAGCCAGGAUGGUCUCCAUCUCCUGACCUCGUGAUCCGCCCGCCUCGGCCUCCCAAAGUGCUGGGAUUACAGGCGUGAGCCACCGUGCCCAAGCCUGACUAACAUUUUAAUAACUACGCUUAGGCAAAAUAGUAAAAGGACAAAGUCUCCCACUUACUCUCUUUCUGGGGACUGACUGGCUUGGGCGCUGGCUGAAACCCAGUGUCUUCACUCCCUGUGUGACCUCGGGCAGGCCCCUUCCCCCUCAGUUAGCUGCAGGCAGGUGUUGGACUAGAUCUGUGGUUUUCUGACCUGGGUUCCACAAAGCAAGCUCAGGGACUGUCCUGCGGAUGAAGAAGACCAGCAGCAAAGCAGGCAGAGCUCUGCCUCCUGGGGCAAAACAUUUGCAAUUAAUGACACUGAAAAGAAUGUGCAAAUCCCCAGUCUCCUCUCCUUCCCGUCAGUGUCCAGCCCAGCCCUUUGAACUGAGUGGUAAGCUCAUUCUGGAACCAGAGACAAAGCCUAAACAGCCACUGGAAGGUCUGGGACCCACAUCAGCCCCCACAUCUGCCCUGCCUUCUCAUCGAAGACAUAUUUUGUGCGCAUGCCUGGUGAAAACUUCUUAAUGACAGCUCUGCCCAUCCCUGUAACUGGCUUCUACCCAGGCAUAUCCCUUCUCCUCUGCUUCACCUACCAGACCUCUUCACCAAAGUGUGCCAGCACUAAAAGAAACAUUUAAAAUCAAAAUUAGGUGAAGCACCACCACCAUUAUGAGAUUCUAUAGUGUCUUAAUGUUCACCCAGUUGAGAUUCUCUGCUAAAUUAGACAUGGAAAAUUGGAAUUGAUUGCUCGCAUGUGGGGCUUAAUUAAACGCUCUAUUUUUUCUCCCUGGUAAUGUCCCAGGA